ACAAAGAGCGGCCGGCGGUACGGGGGUGGUGCCGCGCUCCUGGCCCCGCGCGGGCGGACGGCGGAGGCGCCUCCCAGGUGAGCCGGCCCGGGCGUCCGGCGGGACAUUCAGGCGGCUGGUGGGGUCGAGAGUCCGGGGCCGCCCCUGCGUCGCGACCCGCGCCUUAGUCACCAGACCCGGCUCCGGGAGCGCGGCCUCGGGUGCUCCUCGCGGUGCGGGGCGCAGACUCGGCGCAUCUGCUGUGGUGCCUGCUCUUCCGGUCGCCCUCGAGGGCGGGGCGGGGGUCACGCCCUAAAAUACAGCGCCCGCUGGGCCGAACGCUUGAAAACCCGGUUUCCCGACGGCGGCGGCGCGGGCGCCGUGCGAACGAGGGCCCGGGUCCAGCACAGCCCCAAGGCUCGGCCUGAGGCGGGCGGCCUUGGCCGGGGCCCCCCGUGGUAAUGAGCUACGCGGUGCCCGCCGCCUGCCCAGCGCGGGCCGUUUCUCCUGACGCCGCCGGCGUCUGGUCGAGGCCCAGGAUUCCCUCCUGCCAGUGUGGCUGCGGCCCCCCACGGAGCGGGACCCGCGUUCGUGGCGCUUGGGACGGUUGAUUGAAAGGGUGUAGAAGUCUGUUGCGAAUUUUAUCUGUUGUACUCGUUUUGCAGAUUCGCCCCUUUCCUCCCGCCUGUGCGCGCAGUCACACACACCAUGUGGGAGUCUCUGAUCGCGUUGGGUUCAUAAUCAUCGAUCGUGCCUGGGUACUGAUGCCCCAUUGUUAGGAGCUCUGUGUGGGGCUGUAUGUUUGCACAGGACUCACGUGAGGAAGGGUGGCCACGUUUCUUUCUGCUCUGUGAGACUUAGGCCAAGCCCUGGAACUAGGGAGGAGGUUCAGGAAGAGACCCAUGAAGCUGGCGGGGCCUUGGAGAAGGGCAAGUGAUUUUCAAGGUCAGUAGUAAGAGGGGUCAUGAGUAAUGCCUGCUAUGGGAUGGAUGAAGAAGAGAACCACUAUGUCUCGCAGCUCAGGGAAGUCUACAGCAGCUGCGACACCACGGGGACUGGCUUUCUGGACCGCCAGGAGCUGACCCAGCUCUGCCUUAAGCUUCACCUGGAGCAGCAGCUGCCCGUCCUCCUGCAGACGCUUCUCGGAAACGACCAUUUCGCCAGGGUUAACUUUGAGGAAUUUAAGGAAGGUUUUGUGGCUGUGUUGUCUUCAAAUGCUGGUGUUCGCCCCUCAGAUGAAGACAGUAGUUCUUUGGAAUCAGCUGCCUCCAGUGCCAUCCCUCCAAAGUAUGUGAAUGGUUCUAAGUGGUAUGGCCGUCGGAGCCGGCCUGAGCUAUGUGACGCUGCCACAGAAGCCAGACGCGUGCCGGAGCAGCAAACCCAGGCCAGCCUGAAAAGUCACCUCUGGCGCUCAGCGUCUCUGGAGAGCGUGGAGAGUCCCAAGUCAGAUGAAGAGGCCGAGAGCACUAAAGAAGCUCAGAAUGAAUUAUUUGAAGCACAAGGACAGCUGCAGACCUGGGAUUCUGAGGACUUUGGGAGCCCCCAGAAGUCCUGCAGCCCCUCCUUUGACACCCCAGAGAGCCAGAUCCGGGGCGUGUGGGAAGAGCUGGGGGUGGGCAGCAGCGGACACCUGAGCGAGCAGGAGCUGGCUGUGGUCUGCCAGAGCGUCGGGCUCCAGGGACUCGAGAAAGAGGAACUCGAAGACCUGUUUAACAAACUGGAUCAAGACGGAGACGGCAAAGUGAGUCUUGAGGAAUUCCAGCUUGGCCUCUUCAGUCAUGAGCCCGCGCUACUUCUAGAGUCUUCCACUCGGGUUAAACCGAGCAAGGCUUGGUCUCAUUACCAGGUCCCAGAGGAGAGCGGCUGCCACACCACCACAACCUCAUCCCUCGUGUCCCUGUGCUCCAGCCUGCGCCUCUUCUCCAGCAUUGACGAUGGUUCUGGCUUCGCUUUUCCUGAUCAGGUCCUGGCCAUGUGGACCCAGGAGGGGAUUCAGAAUGGCAGGGAGAUCUUGCAGGCUUGCUGCUUCCAGAGCCUGGACUUCAGCGUGGACGAGAAGGUGAACCUUCUGGAGCUGACCUGGGCCCUUGACAACGAGCUCAUGACAGUGGACAGUGCCGUCCAGCAGGCAGCCCUGGCCUGCUACCACCAGGAGCUGAGCUACCAGCAAGGGCAGGUGGAGCAGCUGGCAAGGGAGCGUGACAAGGCAAGGCAGGACCUGGAGAGGGCCGAGAAGAGGAACCUGGAGUUUGUGAAAGAGAUGGACGACUGCCACUCCACCCUGGAGCAGCUCACGGAGAAGAAAAUCAAGCAUCUGGAGCAGGGGUACCGGGAAAGGCUGAGCCUCCUGCGGUCUGAGGUGGAGGCGGAGCGAGAGCUGUUCUGGGAGCAGGCCCACAGGCAGAGGGCCGCGCUGGAGUGGGACGUGGGGCGCCUGCAGGCUGAGGAGGCUGGCCUCCGCGAGAAGCUGACCCUGGCCCUGAAGGAAAACAGUCGCCUACAGAAGGAGAUUGUGGAAGUGGUGGAAAAGCUUUCGGAUUCGGAGAGGCUGGCCCUGAAGCUGCAGAAGGACCUGGAGUUUGUGCUGAAGGACAAGCUGGAGCCACAGAGUGCAGAGCUCCUGGCCCAGGAGGAGCGGUUCGCAGCAGUCCUGAAGGAAUACGAGCUCAAGUGCCGGGACCUGCAGGACCGCAACGAUGAGCUGCAAGCUGAGCUGGAAGGCCUGUGGGCGCGGCUGCCCAAGAACCGGCACAGCCCCUCAUGGAGCCCGGAUGGGCGCAGACGGCAGCUCCCUGGACUCGGCCCAGCAGGCAUUUCAUUCCUGGGUAAUUCUGCUCCAGUGAGUAUAGAAACGGAGCUGAUGAUGGAGCAGGUAAAGGAGCAUUACCAAGACCUCAGGACCCAGCUGGAGACCAAGGUAAAUUACUACGAAAGGGAAAUUGCGGCACUGAAAAGGAACUUUGAGAAGGAGAGGAAGGACAUGGAGCAGGCUCGCAGGCGCGAGGUCAGCGUGCUGGAGGGUCAGAAGGCCGACCUGGAGGAGCUCCACGAGAAGUCUCAGGAGGUCAUCUGGGGCCUGCAGGAGCAGCUGCAGGACACAGCCCGCGGCCCCGAGCCUGAGCAGAUGGGCCUGGCACCCUGCUGCACCCAGGCACUGUGUGGCCUGGCCCUGCGGCAUCACAGCCACCUGCAGCAGAUCAGGAGAGGAAGUGCCUGGUCAUCGCAGACAGGCUGCUGCUCAGCUGGCACCCACUGUCCUGUGGAGAGCAUUGGCCCCGGCUUAGAAGAGGACGGGCCCUCCCACCACACUGGCCAGGCCACCCCCAGCCUGACAGAAAGUCAUCUUUCCGGCCGGAUGCGGUGGCUCACACCUGUAAUCAGCACUUUGGGAGGCCAAGGCGGGAGAGAGGCUGAGGCGGAGCUGAGUGGAGAGCUGUCGGGGCUGGGAGCCCUGCCCGCUCGCAGAGACCUGACCUUGGAGCUGGAGGAGCCGCCGCAGGGACCCCUGCCACGCGGGAGCCAGAGGUCGGAGCAGCUGGAGCUGGAGAGGGCACUGAAGCUGCAGCCCUGUGCGAGCGAGAAGCGCGCCCAGAUGUGCGUAUCGUUGGCCCUCGAGGAGGAGGAGUUGGAGCUUGCCCGCGGGAAGCGAGUGGACGGGCCCUCCCUGGAAGCAGAGAUGCAGGCCCUGCCGAAAGAUGGGCUGGUGGCAGGAAGUGGCCAGGAGGGCACACGUGGCCUCCUACCACUGCGUCCGGGCUGUGGGGAGCGGCCACUGGCCUGGCUGGCCCCAGGUGAUGGCAGAGAGUCUGAGGAGGCGGCAGGAGCCGGGCCUCGCCGCAGGCAAGCCCAGGACACAGAAGCUACGCAGAGCCCGGCCCCCGCCCCUGCCCCGGCAUCCCACGGCCCCUCAGAGAGGUGGUCACGCAUGCAGCCCUGUGGAGUGGAUGGGGAUAUUGUCCCAAAGGAGCCAGAGCCUUUCGGCGCGAGCGCAGCGGGGCUGGAGCAGCCUGGAGCCCGGGAGCUGCCUCUGCUGGGAACAGAGAGAGACGCCUCGCAAACCCAGCCACGGAUGUGGGAGCCACCCCUGAGGCCGGCCGCUUCGUGCAGGGGACAGGCUGAGAGGCUACAGGCCAUUCAGGAAGAGCGAGCACGAAGCUGGAGCAGGGGCACCCAGGAGCAGGCCUCGGAGCAGCAGGCCCGGGCCGAGGGCGCCCUGGAGCCUGGGUGUCACAAGCACAGUGUGGAGGUUGCCAGGAGAGGGUCCUUGCCAUCCCACCUCCAGCUCGCAGACCCGCAGGGUUCCUGGCAGGAGCAGCUUGCUGCCCCAGAAGAGGGGGAGACCAAAAUAGCGCUGGAGAGAGAGAAGGAUGACAUGGAAACCAAACUUCUACAUCUGGAAGACGUCGUCCGGGCUCUGGAGAAACAUGUAGAUUUGAGAGAGAACGACAGACUGGAGUUCCAUAGACUUUCUGAAGAAAACACUUUGUUGAAAAACGAUCUGGGAAGGGUUCGGCAAGAGCUUGAAGCUGCAGAAAGUACUCACGAUGCACAGAGGAAGGAAAUUGAGGUUUUAAAGAAAGACAAGGAAAAGGCCUGCUCUGAGAUGGAGGUGCUCAACAGACAGAAUCAGAACUACAAGGAUCAAUUAUCCCAGCUCAAUGUCAGGGUUCUUCAACUGGGACAGGAGGCUUCUACCCACCAGGCCCAAAACGAGGAGCAUCGUGUGACCAUUCAGAUGUUAACACAGAGCCUGGAGGAGGUGGUUCGCAGUGGGCAGCAGCAGAGUGACCAAAUCCAAAAACUUAGAGUUGAACUUGAAUGCCUGAAUCAGGAACAUCAGAGCCUGCAGCUGCCAUGGUCAGAGCUGACCCAGACCCUUGAGGAAAGUCAAGACCAGGUGCAGGGAGCUCACCUGAGGCUGAGGCAGGCCCAGGCCCAGCACUUGCAGGAGGUCCGGCUGGUGCCCCAGGACCGUGUGGCCGAGCUGCAUCGCCUGCUCAGCCUUCAGGGAGAGCAGGCCAGGAGGCGCCUGGAUGCACAGCGGGAAGAACAUGAGAAACAGCUGAAAGCCACAGAAGAGCGGGUGGAAGAGGCGGAGAUGAUUCUGAAGAAUAUGGAAAUGCUCCUCCAAGAGAAAGUGGAUAAGCUGAAGGAGCAGUUUGAAAAGAACACGAAGUCCGACCUGCUGCUGAAGGAGCUGUACGUGGAGAACGCCCACCUGGUGAGAGCACUUCAGGCCACCGAGGAGAAGCAGCGAGGCGCCGAGAAACAAAGCCGCCUCUUGGAAGAAAAAGUUCGCGCUCUCAACAAACUCGUCAGUAGGAUUGCCCCCGCAGCCCUCUCUGUGUAAAGACAGAUUAUUUUCUAGGAUUCAUUCGAAAGCACAUCUUUUAAAUUAAGCCACUGUGCUGCCUUAGAUUCCGUGGGUCAUGAGCCAUGAGUCCUGGGACAUCUGAGGAUUGGGAUUCUUUGUUCACCCCGCAGAUAGUUAAUGAAUGGUCUGCCCUGGGCAAGAUGGAGGUGGGGGCUGGGGGAAUAUGCAUGUUGCAGAAGCCGGCGUUUUUAUUAGCGGUCCUGAGUAAUUUCCCUUGGCAAAAUUCCCAGUUUUGCCACUCUCUGGAGCCAGAUCCUGGGAGCUGUCAGCAAGGAGCAGGUAAGUGAGCAGUUAUGGACAGCACUUUCCAUGUGGUGCUUCCGACCCUGGCUGUCAGAGUGAAAUGUAAAGUCAGGGCUCUGUACAGUUUUGCCAUUUCACUGUUCUGCUUUAAGCUUAGCUUAUUAGAACUCUUGGUGGAGGGUGCGUACACACAUUCCAGAAAAGGCUUCACUCGCUGGGAACGUCAACCCAGCGAGAAAGGAGGGGAAGCCCCUUCUCCGGGGACCUUAUCUGUGGACUCAGGAAUGAUGGUGUUUAUUGCAAAUGCACAAUCUUUUUCCCAUUGAAAUGUCAUCACACUGGAAAUUGUACUAUAUGUAAAAAAAAAAAAAAGUAUAGUUUUAUAUUUGAAAUGUAUGCAAAUUAUGGCCAUAUGGCUGAUUGGAAUGUACUACUGUAAUAUAAAAAGUCACUGUAUUUGCAAUAAAUUCUUUUCUAUUAAAAUUGA